CAUUCUGCUUCUUGCUCUCCAGAUGAUUCUGACUUAGAACCAGUGGUGAGAAUUCUGAUCGAAUCCAACUCUAUCAUAAAGGAAAGGAAGCCAAGUGACAUUAAGCAAAGAAAUUCUAUAAGGACUAGGACACAGCUCCCCCAAGGCCUAUGCCAGUAUUAGUUCCUCGGAAAUAAUACUACCAUGAUUUCCUAUUUCCAGAAACCUCAGUGCUGCCACUAAAUGGUUACCUUCUUCAUAUACAUUCAUGUAUCUGAUUACUUCUUUGACAGAACCCUGGCGGGGGGAACCUUAUAUCAAUGAACAGGAAUUAUAAAGAGGAAGAACUCAGCUUGAUAGAAUAAAGGAUUUCCUGUGUCUAAAGAUGGAACGGGCUUUGGGUGAGCAUCUGAACUCAUCACUGAAGGUGAUUUAAGCUUAAGAUGUGUGCAGAGCCAUUUAACAGAACUGACUGAGGGGCUCUGGCCCCCAAAUCUUUCUUUCGGAGAUCUACUUGAAUGUGUGUAAAGUUCCACUCUGAAUCAUUCCUUUGGGGAUCAGGAAUUUCCAGCUCUUCUCGAAAAGAUGUGGAAACUGAGAUUAUUACCCAAUUUUAUGCAGCAAGUCACUGGCAGAGCUGAGAGGAAAAUCAAGAUCUGGCUCUAGACUCUGAAGGCUGAGCUCGAACUGCCACCUCUGCCAGCAGGACCAUGUGUACCAGCUUGACCACUUGUGAGUGGAAGAAAGUCUUCUAUGAGAAGAUGGAGGUGGCAAAGCCAGCGGACAGCUGGGAGCUCAUCAUAGACCCCAACCUCAAGCCCAGUGAGCUGGCCCCUGGCUGGAAGCAGUACCUGGAGCAGCACGCCUCAGGCAGGUUCCACUGCUCCUGGUGCUGGCACACCUGGCAGUCUGCCCAUGUGGUCAUCCUCUUCCACAUGUUCCUGGACCGCGCCCAGCGGGCGGGCUCGGUGCGCAUGCGCGUCUUCAAGCAGCUGUGCUAUGAGUGCGGCACGGCGCGGCUGGACGAGUCCAGCAUGCUGGAGGAGAACAUCGAGGGCCUGGUGGACAACCUCAUCACCAGCCUGCGCGAGCAGUGCUACGAGGAGGAUGGUGGCCAGUACCGCAUCCACGUGGCCAGCCGCCCGGACAGCGGGCCGCAUCGUGCAGAGUUCUGUGAGGCCUGCCAGGAGGGCAUCGUUCACUGGAAGCCCAGCGAGAAGCUGCUGGAGGAGGAGGUGACCACCUACACCUCUGAAGCCUCCAAGCCGAGGGCCCAGGCGGGAUCCGGCUACAACUUCUUGUCUCUUCGCUGGUGCCUCUUCUGGGCCUCUCUCUGCCUGCUCGUUGUUUACCUGCAGUUCUCCUUCCUCAGUCCUGCCUUCUUUUAGUGGAGCUGGUUAAGGGUGGGAGAGGGCACAUGGGCUUGAGAGUGGGGAGGACACAGUCUGGACUUGAUCCUGCUACAGAUUCAACAUAUGACUGGACAAUCCGGUCACCUCUCUGGGCCUCAGUUAAUGCAUCUGCGGAAUGAGAGGAUUGCAUUAGAAGAUAGGCAAUGAUUCUUUCACUGGAUGUGACAAUAAUUGGGGGAAGGGGAAAAGGGUGUAAUAAAGGUUUUAGAGCUUGC